GAGGGCGGGGCCCGUCUGGGGCGCCGGCGGGUGCGUUUGAAUCUGGUCCGAGCGCGGGAAACGGCGGGUCCCCGAGCCCAGUACCAGACCUCCUGUGCGAAGAGUAACCUGCUCUUCGGACUGAUAACUGGAUGGUGAGAUGACUCCUUACCUUGAAAGUAGCAUUCUGGCUGCAGGGCUGAGGUCUUAUGCACAUAUGGUACAAGAAACAUGGAAUAUUGCCACUUUGGGAGAUAGAUUGAAAAAUUAACCAUUAAAAAAUUACAGUCACUAAUAUAAGAGGGAAAAUGGGAAAUAUAGGAAUAAGUUUGGUAGUCUAGAGGAAGUGUAUUACUGUAAGUUGGACUAACAUGCCAAAGAGGUACACUUGGAAAUAGAGCAAACAAGAAAAGUGACCAGAACUAUGAAAAAGUGGAGAGUGUUCACAGACUUGCCGGGCGAAGAUGUAUGAUUCCAUGUGUUUGCUGCACCUUAUUGGAUUAUUUUUCUAAAAUCAUGAAUUUGUCCUAGCCACUAUUCAUUAUGCUUGUUACUGGCCACUCUCCCUUCCCUCCCCAUUUUCUUUGUCAGUGAAAAAUGUGCCAGUCAUGCUUGAUUUAAAGAGGGAGACACGUUGUCGUUAGGCAAUUUCAUCAUUGCAUGAACAUCACAGAGUGGACUUGCCUACACCUAGAGGUGUAGCCUACACACAUAGGCUGUAUGGUGUAGCCUACUGCUCCUAGAAUGUUACUGUACUGAAUACUGUAGGCAACUGUAAUACAAUGGCAAGUAUUUGCAUCGCUAAACAUAUCUAAGCAUAGAAAAAGCACAGUAAAAAUAUGGCAUUAUAAUCUUAUGGGACCACGGUCAUACAUGUGGUCUGUUGUUGACUGAAAUGUUAUGUGGUCCAUGACCGUAGUUCAUAGUUCAGCCAUUUGAGUUGAGGAAUGAGAUGACCAGACUUCACUGUUAACUUAUUUCGGGAGUCAUUAAACUGAGGUUAUUUUUGCUUUGUUCAAUUUGGACAUUAAAAUCUAGUAUUAUAUGUUUAAGAUGACUCUCUGUCCCCAUAAUUAUUGGCAAUAAUUUUCCAUAUUGCUCUAUUUAUAAUGGUGCAGGUGGUUUUCAUUUAUUUUUAAAGUGAGGGGGCUCCUACUGCAAAUGUGUUCCAUCAUUUGCUAUUACCUCAUCUUUAGGUUGAUGUUUUUUCAGUAGGGCACCAGUAGCACCAGGUAUUGUGAAUGCGAAAUAGAAUUUCCUGGAAAAACACAGGCAGGAUGGAGGGUAUACAAAGUCCCCUGAGCUCUCAUUAUCCCGAAGGGGUGGGAGGAGGGUGCUGUGGUUGAGCAUGCCUAAUGCAUAGUCUAACAAGAUCCCAGGUGACCCCCGGGGCCACUGUUUUCCAUCUCACUUUGAAUAACAAGAUGACACUAACAGUGGGAUUUUUUUGAUGGAGGAAUGGCCUUUAGAAAGGGAGCAUCUUCAGAAUCUGCAGCUGGGAUCAGAUUGUUCUUUUGUUGAAUCAACUCAGCUCUGCCGAGCCAGCAUCUUGCUAAGGGUUACAAAAUAAAUGCCAUUUGAACAGUGCCAUCUGUCAUGGAAAAACGUGAGACGUUUGUACAAGCCGUGUCUAAGGAGCUGGUUGGAGAGUUUUUGCAAUUUGUUCAACUUGAUAAAGAGGCCUCUGAUCCUUUCAGCCUAAAUGAAUUACUAGAUGAAUUAUCAAGGAAACAGAAAGAAGAAUUAUGGCAAAGGCUGAAGAAUUUAUUGACAGAUGUGUUGUUAGAAAGCCCAGUGGAUGGGUGGCAGGUAGUGGAAGCCCAGGGUGAAGACAAUAUGGAAACCGAACAUGGCUCAAAAAUGAGAAAAAGCAUAGAAAUAAUUUAUGCAAUUACAUCUGUGAUUCUUGCUUCUGUGUCUGUAAUAAAUGAAAGUGAGAACUACGAAGCCCUACUGGAAUGUGUUAUUAUAUUAAAUGGUAUUUUAUAUGCAUUACCUGAGUCUGAACGAAAACUACAGAGUUCUAUUCAGGAUUUGUGUGUUACCUGGUGGGAGAAAGGCCUGCCUGCCAAGGAAGACACAGGAAAGACAGCCUUUGUCAUGUUACUAAGGAGGAGUCUGGAGACUAAGACAGGUGCAGACGUAUGUCGGCUUUGGCGUAUCCAUCAAGCUUUAUAUUGCUUUGAUUAUGAUUUGGAGGAAAGUGGAGAAAUUAAAGAUAUGUUACUUGAGUGCUUCAUAAAUAUUAAUUAUAUCAAGAAAGAAGAGGGAAGAAGAUUUCUUAGUUGUCUCUUCAACUGGAAUAUCAACUUCAUCAAAAUGAUCCACGGGACCAUUAAAAACCAGUUACAGGGAUUACAAAAGUCUUUGAUGGUAUACAUUGCAGAAAUUUAUUUCAGAGCUUGGAAAAAGGCUUCAGGGAAAAUACUGGAGGCGAUUGAAAAUGAUUGCAUCCAGGACUUCAUGUUCCACGGGAUACACCUUCCGAGGAGGUCUCCAGUGCAUUCCAAAGUGCGGGAGGUUCUGAGUUACUUUCACCAUCAAAAGAAAGUUCGGCAGGGAGUGGAAGAGAUGCUUUAUAGAUUAUAUAAGCCCAUCCUUUGGAGAGGAUUAAAGGCCAGAAACUCUGAAGUUCGAUCAAAUGCUGCAUUGUUGUUUGUUGAAGCAUUUCCUAUUAGGGAUCCAAACCUUCAUGCUAUUGAAAUGGAUAGUGAAAUCCAGAAACAGUUUGAAGAGCUCUAUAGCCUUUUAGAAGAUCCUUACCCGAUGGUCCGUUCCACAGGGAUCCUUGGUGUUUGUAAAAUAACUUCUAAGUACUGGGAAAUGAUGCCCCCGACCAUUCUUAUUGACCUCCUGAAGAAGGUGACUGGGGAACUGGCAUUUGACACGAGCUCAGCUGAUGUUCGUUGUUCUGUCUUUAAGUGUCUGCCAAUGAUUUUGGACAACAAACUGAGCCACCCAUUGUUAGAGCAGCUCCUUCCAGCUCUCAGAUACAGUCUCCACGACAAUUCGGAGAAAGUGAGGGUAGCUUUUGUGGACAUGCUGUUGAAGAUCAAAGCUGUGAGGGCUGCUAAGUUUUGGAAAAUAUGUCCCAUGGAGCACAUUCUGGUUCGUCUGGAAACUGAUUCUCGACCUGUGUCUCGGCGCCUGGUGAGCCUCAUCUUUAAUUCUUUCCUGCCUGUGAAUCAGCCGGAGGAGGUCUGGUGCGAGCGCUGUGUCACCCUGGUGCAGAUGAACCACGCCGCUGCCAGGAGGUUCUAUCAGUACGCCCACGAACACACCGCCUGCACCAACAUAGCAAAGCUGAUUCACGUUAUUCGUCAUUGCUUAAAUGCCUGUAUCCAGAGGGCAGUGAGAGAGCCUCCAGAGGACGAGGAGGAAGAGGACGGAAGGGAGAAGGAGAAUGUGACUGUUCUGGACAAAACACUGUCAGUAAACGAUGUUGCAUGCAUGGCAGGUUUACUAGAAAUCAUUGUGAUUCUCUGGAAAAGUAUUGACAGAAGUAUGGAAAAUAAUAAAGAGGCCAAACUUUACACGAUUAACAAGUUUGCCUCUGUGCUUCCAGAGUAUCUGAAAGUAUUUAAGGAUGAUCGCUGCAAGAUCCCUUUAUUCAUGCUAAUGUCCUUUAUGCCGGCCUCUGCUGUCCCCCCAUUCAGCUGUGGUGUGAUUUCCACGCUGAGAAGCCGGGAGGAGGGCGCUGUGGACAAGAGCUACUGCACUUUGUUGGAUUGCCUCUGCUCCUGGGGGCAGGUGGGGCACAUUCUGGAGCUUGUUGACAACUGGCUGCCCACAGAGCAUGCCCAGGCCAAGAGCAACACAGCUUCUAAAGGUAGGGUGCAGAUCCAUGACACACGCCCAGUCAAACCUGAAUUGGCAUUGGUCUACAUUGAGUAUCUGCUGACUCAUCCAAAGAACCGCGAGUGCUUGCUCUCUGCUCCUCGGAAGAAACUUAACCAUCUUUUGAAAGCCCUUGAAACGUCAAAGGCAGAUCUGGAGUCACUUCUGCAGACACCGGGUGGGAAGCCUCGUGGCUUCAGUGAAGCAGCUGCCCCGCGAGCCUUUGGUCUCCACUGUCGCCUGAGCAUCCAUCUUCAGCACAAGUUCUGCUCAGAAGGAAAGGUGUAUUUGUCCAUGUUGGAAGACACUGGCUUUUGGUUAGAAAGCAAAAUUUUAUCUUUUAUUCAAGAUCAAGAAGAAGACUACCUGAAGCUUCAUAGGGUCAUUUAUCAGCAAAUUAUCCAGACCUACCUGACUGUGUGUAAAGAUGUUGUUAUGGUAGGCCUUGGUGACCAUCAGUUUCAGAUGCAACUCUUACAGCGGAGUCUUGGAAUCAUGCAAACAGUGAAGGGAUUUUUUUAUGUUUCAUUACUUCUUGACAUUCUGAAAGAGAUAACUGGAAGUUCCUUGAUUCAGAAAACAGAUUCAGAUGAAGAAGUUGCAAUGCUGUUGGACACAGUCCAGAAAGUAUUUCAGAAAAUGUUGGAAUGUAUUGCACGGAGCUUCAGGAAGCAGCCGGAAGAAGGCCUGCGGCUGCUUUAUUCUGUUCAGAGGCCUCUUCAUGAGUUCAUUACUGCUGUUCAGUCUCGGCACACAGACACCCCUGUGCACCGGGGUGUACUUUCUACUCUGAUCGCUGGGCCUGUGGUUGAGAUAAGUCACCAGCUACGGAAGGUUUCUGACGUAGAAGAGCUUACCCCUCCAGAGCAUCUUUCUGAUCUUCCACCAUUUUCAAGGUGUUUAAUAGGAAUAAUAAUAAAGUCUUCGAAUGUGGUCAGGUCAUUUUUGGAUGAAUUAAAGGCAUGUGUGGCUUCUAAUGAUAUUGAAGGCAUUGUGUGCCUCACGGCUGCUGUGCAUAUUAUCCUGGUUAUUAAUGCAGGUAAACAUAAAAGCUCAAAAGUGAGGGAGGUUGCAGCCACUGUUCACAGAAAACUAAAGACAUUCAUGGAAAUUACUUUGGAAGAGGAUAGCAUUGAAAGAUUUCUCUAUGAAUCAUCAUCAAGAACUCUGGGAGAACUUUUGAAUUCAUAACCAAGCCAACAUCUCCAGACAUGUAAAAAUAGGGAAAAGUGAUUCAAAUUGAAAUGCCUGUGUAUUUUCCUAUUGUUUUUAAUGUUAAUAACCCAUAUAAUAGGGAAAGGGUGGGAUUUUUUUGUGGGAAUGUGGGAAGGUGGGGGUUAUGGAGGAGAUAACUCAAAACUUCUUCAAUUUUGCCUAGUGCCUGCGUAAAUAAUAUAUUUAAUAUAAAGGACUCCAGGUAUGAAUGGUGUAGAAAUCCAUGAUUCCAAGAAAAAACACUUUUCUAGCAAACCUGGUUGUUUUUAAAAUGACUUUUAUAUAUGUAAUAUUGCUUGGAAACUAUGAGUAAUAAAGCAAUGACAACAUCCAUUUGUUUAUUUGAAAGUAUUAGGGGCCCGGCGCAGUGGCACACGCCUGUAAUCCCAGCACUUUGGGAGGCUGAGGCAGGCAGAUAGAUCACUUGAGGUCAGGAGUUCAAGACCAGCCUAGACAACAUGGUGAAACCCCGU